GCGCCUCCUGCCGCCUCCUAGCGGCCCGGGCCGCGACCACGCUGCCCGCCCCGCCCCGAGCCCGGGGCCCCGCGCUCCGCUGCAGUGAAGGGCGUUGCAUUUCCCGGGGUACCCCGAGCUGCCCUCUUGUGACUCCUUGGCGGGGCGGCUGGUCAGACAAAGUGUGCCUCCGGGCCGGAGGGCGACCCAGAGGAGGGGGAAGAUGCCGCCGGCCACGGGCGGAGGCCUGGCAGAGUCCGAGCUGCGUCCCCGGAGGGGCCGCUGUGGCCCCCAGGCUGCUAGGGCCGCAGGCCGGGACGUGGCCGCUGAGGCUGUGGCGCGAAGCCCCAAACGGCCUGCUUGGGGCUCACGGCGCUUCGAGGCGGUCGGCUGGUGGGCCCUGCUGGCCUUGGUGACGCUGCUGUCCUUCGCCACCCGCUUCCACCGCUUGGACGAGCCGCCGCACAUCUGUUGGGAUGAGACUCACUUUGGAAAAAUGGGAAGUUACUAUAUCAACCGUACAUUUUUCUUUGAUGUGCACCCGCCCCUGGGAAAGAUGCUGAUAGGUCUUGCUGGCUACCUGAGUGGAUAUGAUGGUACCUUUUUGUUCCAGAAGCCUGGGGAUAAAUAUGAGCAUCACAGCUACAUGGGAAUGAGAGGAUUCUGUGCAUUCCUUGGCUCCUGGCUGGUCCCCUUUGCCUACCUCACUGUACUGGAUCUGUCCAAGUCCCUCUCGGCAGCACUGCUCACAGCUGCCCUCCUCACCUUUGACACGGGAUGCCUCACUCUGUCCCAGUACAUCCUCCUUGACCCCAUCCUGAUGUUCUUCAUCAUGGCUGCCAUGCUGAGCAUGGUCAAGUACAACUCUUGCGCCGACAGGCCCUUCUCUGCCCCCUGGUGGUUCUGGCUCAGCCUGACUGGCGUUAGUCUUGCUGGUGCUUUAGGGGUCAAGUUUGUUGGCCUCUUUAUCAUCCUUCAAGUGGGGCUGAACACCAUUGCAGACCUUUGGUACCUGUUCGGAGACCUCAGUCUUUCAUUGGUGACUGUGGGAAAACACCUGACUGCUCGUGUCCUGUGCCUCAUAGUGCUGCCCCUGGCUCUCUAUACAGCCACCUUUGCUGUUCACUUCAUGGUGCUGAGUAAAAGUGGCCCUGGUGACGGUUUCUUCAGUUCUGCCUUCCAGGCCCGGCUUUCAGGGAACAACCUGCACAAUGCUUCCAUCCCUGAACACCUGGCCUACGGCUCUGUGAUCACUGUGAAGAACCUCCGGAUGGCCAUCGGCUAUCUGCACUCCCACAGGCACCUCUACCCCGAGGGCAUUGGUGCCCGUCAGCAGCAGGUCACCACCUAUUUGCACAAGGACUACAACAACCUGUGGAUUAUCAAGAAACAUAACACAAACUCAGAUCCCCUAGACCCUUCCUUCCCAGUGGAGUUUGUAAGACAUGGAGACAUUAUUCGACUAGAACACAAAGAAUGUCCACUUAAAAAAAUCUGGCGAUGGGAGCAGAAAGAAACUUCCCGGAACUUGCACAGUCACUAUCAUGAGGCCCCCAUGACCCGGAAGCACUAUCAGGUCACCGGCUAUGGCAUAAAUGGAACAGGGGACUCAAAUGAUUUCUGGCGGAUUGAGGUCGUAAACAGGAAAUUUGGAAACCGGAUCAAAGUGCUGAGAAGUCGAAUUCGCUUCAUCCAUUUGGUCACAGGUUGUGUCCUGGGCUCCUCGGGAAAGGUUCUGCCCAAGUGGGGCUGGGAGCAGUUGGAAGUUACUUGCACCCCAUACCUGAAAGAAACCCUCAACUCCAUCUGGAAUGUGGAGGACCAUAUCAAUCCCAAGUUGCCAAACAUCAGCCUGGAUGUGCUACAGCCCAGUUUUCCUGAGAUCUUGCUGGAAUCCCACAUGGUCAUGAUCCGGGGGAACAGUGGCCUCAAACCCAAGGACAAUGAGUUCACGUCCAAACCCUGGCACUGGCCUAUCAACUAUCAGGGCCUACGCUUCUCAGGGGUCAAUGACACAGAUUUCCGAGUCUAUCUGCUUGGCAACCCGGUGGUUUGGUGGCUGAAUCUGUUGAGCAUCGCCCUCUACCUCCUCUCAGGGAGCAUCAUUGCUGUAGCCAUGCAGAGAGGGGCACGGCUGCCAGCGGAGGUUGCAGGUCAGGUCCUCUGGGCUCUCCCUCCCCUGACCUGGCGGCAGCAGGGCACCUGCACCCCUGGGGAGGGCCGGCUGCCUGCUGAUGGGCCAUCCUUUGCGUUUACCACCCCACACCUUCCCUUAUCCUUUGCUUUUGAAAGGAAACCAAGGAACCAUGAGAUUAAGAAACUUGCCCCAGGACAUACAGCUAGGUUGUCCCAGGUCCUGCUUCGAGGAGGCGGCCAGGUCCUGCUCGGCUGGACACUCCAUUACUUCCCGUUUUUCCUGAUGGGCCGGGUCCUCUACUUCCACCACUACUUCCCAGCCAUGCUCUUCUCAAGCAUGUUGACAGGCAUUCUGUGGGACACCCUCCUGCGGCUCUGUGCCUGGGGCUUGGCCUCAUGGCCCCUGGCGAGGGGCAUACAUGUGGCGGGAAUCCUGAGCCUGCUCCUGGGAACUGCCUACAGCUUCUACCUCUUCCACCCUCUGGCUUACGGGAUGGUUGGUCCCCUGGCCCAGGACCCCCAAAGUCCAAUGGCAGGACUAAGGUGGCUGGACUCAUGGGACUUUUGAGGCCACUGCAAAGAUUCCAGCCUGGGUCCAGGAACUUCCCAGGAGAGCCAGCUGGGAAGCAGUACUGGACCAUCCGGCCAUGAGGAAGCUGCCUAAGGAGCCCGAAGAAUUCUGCUGCUCACCAGGACCCAGCUCUGGGAGUGCAGCUGGAAUGGAACCCAGCAUUGGAGAGAGCCGGGAGAGAGCCGCAGCUCCGUCCACAGCACCACGGAGAGGACAGCGCCUCUUGGGCUGCUCCCUCGUGCACAGCGCAGGGGAGGAUGGGUGCCAGAGGGUGGGAGUGGGUGCGCGUGUGUGUAUGUGAGGGCAUGUUGUCCAUAUCCCUGUGGAAUACAGACCGUGUAACUGGACAGCUGAGUGUCAUAAACUCUAAAAUAGUCCAGGCUAUAGUAAUAUUUUCUGGUAUUUUUUUCUGUUGGAUUUCUUUGGUUUUGGUUUGUAAGAUCCAUCAAAAAUUCUCAGACCUCUGAGAGGGCCUUGAGGGCAGAGAAUACUGACCUCACCUUGGGAUGUCACCAAAGGCAGAGCAGAUGGGACUGUCAAAGUUGUGCUGCCCUCCCUCCCACAAACAAAUGAAUCCAGCGUGGAGGAAGGCGCGCCGCCCCGAGCUGGAGGGCCUGGCUCCCACCAUGCCCCCCAGUGGCUGCAGGUAGCUGGACUUCCUGCCUGUGACGCACAGAGAGCAGCGGACUCCGGAGCGUCAGCCUGCCUUAGCCCUUGGUUCCUCGUUUUUUGGGAUUGUCACACUGUGACACUCGGGAGGAACGAUGUCCUAUCCUGGGCUGCUCAGUGUUCCCAGGCCCUGUGUGCCAGAGGCCAGGUCUCUCCAAGUGCAUCUAGCCUGGCCUGGAGGGCAAGGCAGAUGCAUUCUCCUGGCUGCUGGGAGAGCCCAUGGGAACCUUGCUUAGCGCCCAAGGUAGAUGAGAGACAGGGCAGGGAAUCUGCGUGGUGCUGGGAUGUGGGGACUCUGGCCUCUCCAGACUAAUGUUCCUGUCACCUGCUGAGCUUUCCCAGUGUCACUUCUGCAGUCCUCCUCUGCUCACCCCUCCCUCACUCCGUGGGCAAUUCCCUUUCUCUCUGUCACUGCUUCAGCAGUGAAGACCCAUGGCACCUAGAAAUGCAUGCCAGCUUCCUGCGUCUACCACUCUGCAGCUCAAACAAGAAGCUCAGAGCUGCCCCUUCCACUUCCUCCCCAAAAGGGAUGAAGAAAACCCUGUGGUAGAACCAAACCACCCAAGGCCAGCCCUUAAGCCUGCCUCCACCUUCCUGGUGCAUGACAAAAUAUUUCUUUUGUCUCAGAGGACUUUGAUGCUUCAAUAUUUAAUGAUGAAUCCGCCACACUCCAUUUUCCCUCCUCUGAAGCUCCCAACAACUCUGACAGGGUCAGAUCUCUUUAAAGCAUCUUCAGGAGGCGGUUGCCACGGAGACUGGAUAUUGGUCCCAGGGACAGGCUGUGCUACCUACUGGGUGGUGGGGAGGGAAGCUUCUGGCCAUGCUUGGGCAUUCAGACCAACCAUCAUUAAUGUUAAUAGAGGAAAUGCAGCAACGUCAAAAGCAAGGCAGGUUGGUUAAUUAGAUCUGGGGCCCGAUGACCUCCCUUUCCCACUGCUACAGCCCUUUUGACUUCCCCCAGCAGGAAGCGCUGUCUGUGCGGCUGAGUCUGGGCCACUUGCUUAAUUGCAUUUCUGGCAGGGAAGGAGAGGAGGGAUGGAGAAGCUCUGCUCGCUGCUUCCACCUCACCGUGUGUCCUCCCCUCCCCUCCCUUCCUCUCCUCCCCACAGGCGGAAUUGCUUUCUUCUGAGCCGGGUGGGCUCUCCUGCAGGGAGAAUGCAGGGGUCUGUGCUUGGCUCUUAGCAAAGCAGGUGGCCCACAGUGACCUCCAGGAGGUGGCUGAUUUUCCUUUGUGCCUUCUUAUUUCUCAGUAGGAACUUGGAAGGGAAGAGCUCUGAAGGAGCCAGAGGGGCAGCCACCUUGCAUGAGGGUGAGGAAGGAGAAGCCCAGCCAGCCUCUACCCAUCCCUCCCUCCCAAUUAGGCUGCACUGGGGCCGAACGCUUCCCUGGGCUCCCACUGCCUUCUAAGGAGCCAAGGAGAAUUCCCUGCCCACUUUCUGUUCCUCCAUGCCCAAACUGGCAGAUGCUUCUCUGGGAGCAAGGCCACAUGGGCUGAUGCAGCUUUGAGUGCUCAGGUUCUGUUUUCUGGAAGUUGCUGGAGAAGGGCUGUCAGGGUGCUUCUAUGAAUAUGGGCUUCAGCUGUAGCACUUGGCAGAAACGUGAUGUGUCCCACAAACUGCUGGUGGAGGAAGAAGAUGUUCGUCAGCCAAUUCAACCUCCAGCCAGCUUCUUGAGCCUAUUUGGUUUAAAAAAAAAAAGUCUUCUAAUCAGAAGCCACUGAUUUUAUAAUAAAUAACACUUGUUUUGAA